GCUUUCUGCACGUCCUCGCCGCCGCGCCGCCAGUCCGUUUGUGCUAGCUCUGGCCGUGAGCCGGCCGCCCGCUGCCGCCGGCCGCCCCGCAGCUGCCUGCGCCCCAGCCGCGCCUCGCGGCCAGCCCGGCUAGCUCAGGUCCGCUCCCGGAGCCCGCGCCCCUCCACGCUGCCCCCUGCCUGUCCCCGGCCAUGCUGUCCCUUCAGUACCCCGACGUGUACCGCGACGAGACCGCCGUACAGGAUUAUCAUGGUCAUAAAAUUUGUGACCCUUACGCCUGGCUUGAAGACCCCGACAGUGAACAGACUAAGGCCUUUGUGGAGGCCCAGAAUAAGAUUACUGUGCCAUUUCUUGAGCAGUGUCCCAUCAGAGGUUUAUACAAAGAGAGAAUGACUGAACUAUAUGAUUAUCCCAAGUAUAGUUGCCACUUCAAGAAAGGAAAACGGUAUUUUUAUUUUUACAAUACAGGUUUGCAGAACCAGCGAGUAUUAUAUGUACAGGAUUCCUUAGAGGGUGAGGCCAGAGUGUUCCUGGACCCCAACAUACUGUCUGACGAUGGCACAGUGGCACUCCGAGGUUAUGCGUUCAGCGAAGAUGGUGAAUAUUUUGCCUAUGGUCUGAGUGCCAGUGGCUCAGACUGGGUGACAAUCAAGUUCAUGAAAGUUGAUGGUGCCAAAGAGCUUCCAGAUGUGCUUGAAAGAGUCAAGUUCAGCUGUAUGGCCUGGACCCAUGAUGGGAAGGGAAUGUUCUACAACUCAUACCCUCAACAGGAUGGAAAAAGUGAUGGCACAGAGACAUCUACCAAUCUCCACCAAAAGCUCUACUACCAUGUCUUGGGAACCGAUCAGUCAGAAGAUAUUUUGUGUGCUGAGUUUCCUGAUGAACCUAAAUGGAUGGGUGGAGCUGAGUUAUCUGAUGAUGGCCGCUAUGUCUUGUUAUCAAUAAGGGAAGGAUGUGAUCCAGUAAACCGACUCUGGUACUGUGACCUACAGCAGGAAUCCAGUGGCAUCGCGGGAAUCCUGAAGUGGGUAAAACUGAUUGACAACUUUGAAGGGGAAUAUGACUACGUGACCAAUGAGGGGACGGUGUUCACAUUCAAGACGAAUCGCCAGUCUCCCAACUAUCGCGUGAUCAACAUUGACUUCAGGGAUCCUGAAGAGUCUAAGUGGAAAGUACUUGUUCCUGAGCAUGAGAAAGAUGUCUUAGAAUGGAUAGCUUGUGUCAGGUCCAACUUCUUGGUCUUAUGCUACCUCCAUGACGUCAAGAACAUUCUGCAGCUCCAUGACCUGACUACUGGUGCUCUCCUUAAGACCUUCCCGCUCGAUGUCGGCAGCAUUGUAGGGUACAGCGGUCAGAAGAAGGACACUGAAAUCUUCUAUCAGUUUACUUCCUUUUUAUCUCCAGGUAUCAUUUAUCACUGUGAUCUUACCAAAGAGGAGCUGGAGCCAAGAGUUUUCCGAGAGGUGACCGUAAAAGGAAUUGAUGCUUCUGAUUACCAGACAGUCCAGAUUUUCUACCCUAGCAAGGAUGGUACGAAGAUUCCAAUGUUCAUUGUGCAUAAAAAAGGCAUAAAAUUGGAUGGCUCUCAUCCAGCUUUCUUAUAUGGCUAUGGCGGCUUCAACAUAUCCAUCACACCCAACUACAGUGUUUCCAGGCUUAUUUUUGUGAGACACAUGGGUGGUAUCCUGGCAGUGGCCAACAUCAGAGGAGGUGGCGAAUAUGGAGAGACGUGGCAUAAAGGUGGUAUCUUGGCCAACAAACAAAACUGCUUUGAUGACUUUCAGUGUGCUGCUGAGUAUCUGAUCAAGGAAGGUUACACAUCUCCCAAGAGGCUGACUAUUAAUGGAGGUUCAAAUGGAGGCCUCUUAGUGGCUGCUUGUGCAAAUCAGAGACCUGACCUCUUUGGUUGUGUUAUUGCCCAAGUUGGAGUAAUGGACAUGCUGAAGUUUCAUAAAUAUACCAUCGGCCAUGCUUGGACCACUGAUUAUGGGUGCUCGGACAGCAAACAACACUUUGAAUGGCUUGUCAAAUACUCUCCAUUGCAUAAUGUGAAGUUACCAGAAGCAGAUGACAUCCAGUACCCGUCCAUGCUGCUCCUCACUGCUGACCAUGAUGACCGCGUGGUCCCGCUUCACUCCCUGAAGUUCAUUGCCACCCUUCAGUACAUCGUGGGCCGCAGCAGGAAGCAAAGCAACCCCCUGCUUAUCCACGUGGACACCAAGGCGGGCCACGGGGCGGGGAAGCCCACAGCCAAAGUGAUAGAGGAAGUCUCAGACAUGUUUGCGUUCAUCGCGCGGUGCCUGAACGUCGACUGGAUUCCAUAAACAGUUUUCGUGCUUCCUCCUGACAGCGACAGAAAACCUCAAGGGCUUUCCCACGUUGACACCAAGAAACCACUGGGCAUAAUGCUUCCCCACGGGAACAUUAUUCCUGCACUCACAGGCUACAGUUGAACAGAACUGCCGUGGGAAUUUUAUCUUUUUUAGGCUUCUCCUUUUUAGCAAGGCCUUGGUGUUUCUUUUUCCACCCUGUCUAGGCACAUGUGGUUUUUUGGUGUUUUUUUUAAGGGCAUGUUGGGAUAAAUAGCUAAAUGGCAACAAACACAUUGUGAAUAUUAGAUUGCUGAAUUAAGGAUCAUAGUCGGGCAUACUUAUCUAUAUCCAUAACCUCUAUAUCUUUAAAUAAAUGUGAGAACUGUUCUCAUGGAGAAGACUUCUUUGCAACAAUAAUAAAUGUUAUUUAAGAAUGACAGGCUUUUACUUCCGGUUUCUUCAUAUUGAGGGGCAACUCCAGAAGUGGAGUUUUCUGUGAGAAUAAAGCAUUUCACCUUUCUGCAACAAGUUAGUUUUCAAGCAGUUAAGUCAUAGAAUGUUUGUUAGCUUUGAAAAUAAGUUGUUCAUCCACUCUGUCUCCCUUGUUUGUUUGUUUGUUAGAGGUGAUGAAGCUGUCAGAGGGGGUUCACUGUCAUAAACAAACACUGACCACUUAGUUGGGUAAAAAUCUGAUCUGGGGCUCUUUUGGUUUGGAUGCCUCCUUUCAAAAAUCACUGGGCUGGAAAAUUCAGAUUAUUCACCUAUUUGUAUAUUGAUUUGUUUACAAAGUAUUCCUAGAAAUCAGAGUUCCUUGGAUCCAAGGAUCCUUGGUUCCAAGAGAUCACAUGAGUAAAUUAUCCAAACAAACAGAUACAUAUAUCCAAGCAUUUCUUACAGUCAGAAAUUUCAGCAUUUCCCAAGCUGUUUCUCCUGCAUAGAUCACUCCUGGAAAUAGAAAUAGUCAUACUUACUUACUGGAAAAAAAAAAAAAAAAGUUUUGGUUUGCCCACCCCCAAGAUUUUUAAGAUAUACUAUUCCUUAAACUUUCAUCCAUAAAAUUUUUUUCAAGGCAUAUAUUUUAACAUUUCAUGAAACAAUGUUCCUUUGAGUAUCAGUUUGGGAAAUGCUGAUCUAACUUAAAACAGUUUUUUUUCCUUUGUCUUGCUUUAUCAGAUGAUAUGAUAAAAAUUAUUAUUUUAUAUAGUAUCUUAACCUUAUAUAAAAUAGCUUAAAAGAUUACUUCAUUAUUCCAAUAAUUUGUACUUUUCCAAGUAAGUCCCAUCUUCCAAGUUGUAUAUGUAUGUGCUUUUAAGAGCACUCUCUCAUUCUCUACGUUUCAAGUUAUGGUCAAAAAUUAGACAUACCAUUUUCUAUCAAGCAUAUCACUGCAUACCAAGCAUAUUGAAAGACAGCUAUAUGGCUUGGUUUUUCUCUACUGGAAUCAUGUUUUCCGUUACUAUUUAGUACGGUACAUAAUACAGUUGUCAUUGAGUAUAAGAUUCACCAUAACUCCUCUGGAAACAAAGUGUGCCAGUAGCUAGUGUUGCAUGCUGAGACUCUGUCGUCAUCACCAUCUACUCAGAUACUGAUACUAGCUAGCUUUGGUGUAACUGCUGACCAGCAUGGCAGGAAAGAAAGAAAAUACAUUUGCAUGGUCAAGCCAGAGGCAGCCUCUUUCCUAGACUAGCUGUGUGGUGUGAAGUACAAAUAGCUGAGUUGGACCCACUGAGUCCAGAGCAUUUUCAAGGUUGCACAGAAUCUAACCAUACUUUCUGAGGUCUGCUUUACAGCAGAAAAUACAGUGUGUAGUGUGUGAGCUUCAGAUAUCAGGACUGGGUUCAAAUCCCAAAUGUCACUUAGCAACUGAUGAGGAGGAGGAGGAAUACAGUAAUACGUUUUUAAUGCCUAGCAUGAUUGGCCUCCAGUUACGAGUUCUCUUUUCCAACCUAAUUUUUGUGUCUAGAUUUUCACAGGACAACUAAUCCCACCAACUAAAGGUAUUUUGGGGAGUAGGGGGAGCUUUAAACAUUAGAAAUAAGACUUGAGAUUGGGCUCCUACCCAGAACUCUAAGGGAUUCUUCUCUAUUUGAUCCCACUUUUCUGUAUCCUGUGCUCUGCCCUUUGGCUCUUUCUUAUGAUUACUCUCUUCUAGCUAUUUUGAAAUGCACAGUAGAUUAUUGUAAACUAUAGACACCCUACUGAUCUAACACUAGGUCUUCUUUCAAACUGUAUAUUUGUAGGCAUUAAUCUCUUCAUCCUCCCUUUCUCUGCCUGCUUUUUUAGCUCCCACAUGAGUGGAGAACAUGGGAUAUUUGUCUUCCUGUGCCUGGCUUAUUUCACUUACCAUAUUGACCUUCAGUUCCAUCCAUGUUGCUGCAAAUGACAGGAUCUCAGUCUUUUUCAUGGCUAAAUCAUAUUCCAUUGUAUAUAUGUACCACAUUUUCUUCAUCUGUUCAUCUGCUGAUGGGCACGUGGGUUGAUUCCCUAUCUUGGCUGUUGUGGAUAGUGCUGCAGUAGACACAGGAGUGCAGAUAUCUUUUUGAUAUACUGAUUUCCUUUCUUUUGGAUUCAUACCCAGUAGUGGAAUUGCUCGAUCACAGAGGACUUAUAUGUUUAGUUUUUUUAGGACUGUUUUGAAAAAGAAAAAGUUGUACAUGUUGCACAGGUGGCCUCACUGCUUUGUCACAAGGCCCUGCUAAGCACACCAGAGCAUUUGUUACCUUAGCAAGAUAAAGUCACAUUUAUGUUCACUAUGGACUUACCUGGAAUAUUAUAAAACUUUCCAAUUAAUCAUGUUUCUUAAAUACUCCCACUAAAGCUUAAGCAGCUACACACACAUGGUGCUACAAGUUUGAAAAGGAUAAGUUUCAACUAAGGAAGCCUGUCACCAGUCUCUCAAGGUUUGUCAGUUUUACCAGCCUCUGGAAGUUCCCAGCAGGCCACAUAGCUAAUGCCCAGAAGGAGUUGCAAAGACUCAAAGGCAGGUUAAGGACAGGCUGGAAAGCUGUGGAGGUUGCUGUAAAGAGGCAAAGGUCAUACUGUUGGGGUGGUCAGGCCAGUGGGAUGAGGACUGAGGCCCUUGAAGGAGGAACAUUGAGCCAUUCUCAUCCUCCAUAUCUCAGGGGCUGAAGGUGCAGAGAGAAAAUGUCCUGCCCUCAUCCAGUUGAUAUUCCAGGGAGGAGACAGAUGGUAAAUUAUCUUGCUCAUGUUUACCCUGUGCCACCCGCUGCAAGCACUCUGUGUGGAUGAAUGUUUGUCCUCACACAACCUUAGGAAGCACAUAAUACCUUUUCCCCAUUUGGCAAAGGUCCAAGUUCCCCAGCCAGGAGGUGGGCAGGCAGGGCAGUAACCCCAGGAGCUGGGCCUUGGAUACUGCACUCUUUUUUUGGGAUGGAGUUUUGCUGUUACGGCCCAGGCUGGAGUGCAAUGGCGCUAUCUCAGCUUACUGCAACCUCCACCUCUUGGGUUCACGUGAUUCUCCUGCCUCAGCCUUCCCAGUAGCUGGUAUUACAGGCGCAUACCAUCAUUCCCGGCUAAUCUUUUUGUAUUUUUAGUAGAGAUGGGGUUUCACCAUGUUGGCCAGGCUGGUCUUGAACUCCUGACCUCAGGUGAUCCACCCACCUCAGCCUCCCAAAAUGCUGGGAUUACAGGCAUGAGCCACCAUGCCCAGCCGAAACAGCUCUCUUACUGCUGUUGUCUGAGUGUUUAUGUCCUCCCCGAAAUGUAUAUGUUGAAAUCGUAAAUCCCAAAGUGAUGGAAUUAGGAGGCAGGGCCUUCAGGAGGCGAUGGGUCAUGAGAGCGGAAUCCUCAUGAAUGGGACUGGUGCCUUUAUAUUAGAGCCCAAGGAGAGACCCCCCCGCCCCAUCCCUUCCACCAUGUGAGGACACAGGAGACGGUGUCACCUAUGAACCAGGAAGCAACCCUCAUUAGACACCAAAUCUGCCAGUGCCUUGAUCUUAGAUGUCCCAGACUCUAGGACUGUGAGAGAGCAAUUUCUGUUGUUGACAACCCACCAGUUUAUGGUAUUUUCUUAUAGCAGCUUAAACAGACUAAGAUACCCACGAGUCUAUUAACAAGAUAAUAAACAAAGUAUAAUUUCAGGAAUUAACAAGAAACAGGAAUAAAAAGAGCUGUGAAGAAACAAAGUGGGGCAAAUGAAUAGUCCGUGAGAAGGAAUGCUAUUUGAGUCGAGGUCAGGGUGCCUCUUUCAGGAAGCAACAUUCGGACAAAGACCCGAACGGAAUGAGGGGACAAACAAUGGGCAACGUUUUGGGGGUUGGUGAGGACAGCAGCAAUGGGCAGAGCCUGAGGCAGGAACCAGCCAGGCCUUUGGAGGAAGAGCAGGAAGCCAGUGUGGGGGGAACAGGGAGCCAGGCGAGGCCUGGAGGAUACACUAGAGAUGGCAGGCAGCUCAGUCAGGUGAAGCCACUGAGAGAUGAAAGCCGACAACACUGUGGGAAACUGACAGCAGGAGAGCCUAGGGAAAAGCGGGGUGGUUAUUCAAAGAGCAGGUUGCUUAGCACCUUUAAGGAAUUUUGGGGGUGGGGGCAGCAGGAACCCACCAUCACAAAAAUCACUGACAUGCCAUAUCAUGGAUGAAUCUCAAAAACAUUAUAAGUGAAAGAAGCCAGACACAAAUGACUGGGUAUAGUCUGAUUAAGUGAAAUAUCCUGAAAAGGCAGUUCUAUAAAGAUAGAAUGUAGAUUAGUGGGUACCUGGAGUUGGUGGUGAAGAUGGUAAUUAACUACUUGGGCAUAAAGGAUCUAACCGGGAUGACAAAAAUGUUCUAAAACUGGAUUUCAGUAACGGUUGCACAACCUGGUAAAUGUAUUAAAAAGUCAUUGAAUUGUACACUUGAAAUGUAUGAAUUUUAUGGUUUGUAAAUCAUAAUGUUAUCGAAAUAAUCUCUGGUAGUGAAAUAAAGAGAAAAAAGAGCAA